CGAAGCCUGGCCUGCUGGGUCCUUUUCCCGUCAUCCCCAGCCAGAUUUAGCUGCUGACAGCUGCUUGGGACUCUGCCGCCAGGGCCUGGCCCAGACCUGCCUGCCUCUCUCCUCUCCCUCAGUGACUCCUGAGCCACAGCCCCUCCAUGGCCCAGAAGGAAGAGGCUGCUGUGGCCACUGAGGCUGCCUCCCAGAAUGGGGAGGAUCUGGAGAACCUGGACGACCCUGAGAAGCUGAAAGAGCUGAUUGAGCUGCCGCCCUUUGAGAUUGUCACAGGAGAACGGCUGCCUGCCAACUUCUUUAAAUUCCAGUUCCGGAAUGUGGAGUACAGUUCCGGGAGGAACAAGACCUUCCUCUGCUAUGUGGUUGAAGCACAGGGCAAGGGGGGCCAAGUGCAGGCAUCUCGGGGAUACCUAGAGGAUGAGCAUGCGGCUGCCCAUGCAGAGGAAGCUUUCUUCAACACCAUCCUGCCAGCCUUCGACCCAGCCCUGCGGUACAAUGUCACCUGGUAUGUGUCCUCCAGCCCCUGUGCAGCGUGUGCUGACCGCAUUAUCAAAACCCUUAGCAAGACCAAGAACCUGCGUCUGCUCAUUCUGGUGGGUCGACUCUUCAUGUGGGAGGAGCCGGAGAUCCAGGCUGCUCUGAAGAAGCUGAAGGAGGCUGGCUGUAAACUGCGCAUCAUGAAGCCCCAGGACUUCGAAUAUGUCUGGCAGAAUUUUGUGGAGCAAGAAGAGGGUGAAUCCAAGGCCUUUCAGCCCUGGGAGGACAUUCAGGAGAACUUCCUAUACUACGAGGAGAAGUUGGCAGACAUCCUGAAGUAGGGCAACUGGGCUUUGCCUCACGUAUUCCUGCUGCCACCAAGAGACAGCAAUGACAUGUACAGCCAUCUGGGACAUGCCUGUCUUCCUAAUACCAUUUGGAGCUGGACAACAUUUGACACCAACCAAUCAUACUGGACAAGGCCCUUAGAGGACUUGAAAUAUACUUCUCAUGCUGUAGUUUAUUUAGGCUGUGACUCUCUCUCUAAUGCUGCUCUCGGGAAGGACGAAAGUGACCUGCAAGGAGAGAAAUGCAACCAUACAUGGGCUCCAGUCAACUAUGGGACUGAAGGUCCUAAUUGCUCACCCAAGGGGGCUGCUUAACACAAACAGCCUCAGACCCGAGGUUUAGAUUUCUGAAAUAUGCAUUUUAUGUUAAGUUGGGUAUUUUUUUAAAAAAAGAAAAACAGCAACAUUAAUAAAAGAAGUGGUGUGUUUUUCCCGUGGCCAGAUUUUUAAGAAACUUGAACAUCUGGAAGUUGCCACAGACAAGCGAGCUAGUCCAGACACAGGGACACUCCAGGCUAUGAACCAAGCCAUGGUUAAACCAAGACUUGCCUAGACAAUGCAGAAUAACUCUCCCAUACAGACUUCUUACGACAAUCAAGUGAGGGCCUUUCCCUUCUCUGAAGGCAAGUAAUAGGGCAGAAGGUGGAACAAAAAGCAUGAGAAAUCUAAGGUAGCCACAUCCCAAAUGCCAGUUAAUAAGCAACUAGCUUCUUUAUUAGAGAGGAGCGGGUGAAAAGUAGUAGUUUAAUGUUCAGAUAUACAAUCAUUUAAAAGUAUUCAAUACAUGGUGUUUGAUGGUAAUGGCA